AGUGAGAAGUCUGGCCAUCGGUAGAGGGAUGCAGCCACUACCAACCACAGUAUGGCAGAGAAGUAGCAGAGAAGAAAUAAAAGAAAUCCCCUCUCACUCUCCAAUUCUGUUGUUGCCUCCAUGCGCCAAUCCAAACCGAAAGCCAGAAGGCAAAACUACCUGGUGUGUCUGGAAGUGUCUGUUUCUGGAAUUCCACUCACAGGGGAAAAUUAGCCUGAACCAGAUGGCUUGAAACAGUCCUCAUGGGUGAGGGGUGGAAGGAGACACUGGAAAAGGGGACUGAAAUCAGCUUUAGGAACUUUCUGUCCUUUAAUCUCAAGAAUACAGAAAGUGAAUGUAACAUGUUAUGAGAAACCUCAUAUUGCCUGUAGAUCUUCACUUUCAAUACACACACACGCACACGCACACGCACACAGGCUACUGCUAUUGGCAAAUGCCUCCUCUCCAGCCAUCAGAGGAAAGAAGCUAUCCAGACGGUCCCAACGCACCAGGGAUAGAUGGAGUCUCCGCAGCCCUCAGCUGCAGCGGACUGGUCUGUGGAAUCACAGCGAGGAAGGUGUUGCGAGGAAAUCCCUUGCAUGCUGUGUGGUGUGUUAAAAAUGCAGCAUCAUCCUCUCUGCUCCUUUUCUUCGCUGAAAAGCAGAAUUCGAGGGCACAGGGAAACUGGAGGGGCGAGAAGGCUGUCUCCUGGAGCCCUGGGGCUGUCUCCCUCCAUGCCCCACUCCUUGGGCUCUAAUUGCCCUUGCUCCAAUGGGCCAGCAGCACCUUCACCAUUUAUUUCCUCUUCAAUUCACUCCAGCGGGGAGGGAAGAGGGAACACAAAACUCUAAAAAUAACUGUCAGCAUCUUAAAAAAAGAAAAAAGCUUAUCUGCCCCCCCACCCCCAACGUGCUCCCGCCCUUCUCCCUCCUCUCCCCCCCUCAGCCCCCCCCCCCUUUAUGGGGCACAUGUCUGCUUCUUACAACACCGAGGCACAUGGUUCCAGUUAGGCACCGAACCCCACCAAGACAGAGAGGAAAUCCACAUCUGUGGGACGCUCCACACGGAACCACCUCCAGCGAGGGAGGCCAGGGGACUGCAGCACCGAGAUGAAGGGCUAGACCGAGGGAACGCUGCUCAUGCGACGGCCGGGAGCGCCUGCGAGCUGGAUCUGGUGGAGGAUGCUGCGGCAGGUGCUUCGCAGAGGGCUCCAGUCGUUCUGCCACAGGCUGGGUUUGUGCGUGAGCCGGCACCCGGUCUUUUUCCUCACCGUGCCCGCAGUCCUGACAAUCACCUUCGGCCUCAGCGCGCUCAACCGCUUCCAGCCCGAGGGCGACCUGGAGCGCCUGGUCGCUCCCAGCCACAGCCUGGCCAAGAUCGAGCGCAGCCUGGCCAGCAGCCUUUUCCCCCUGGACCAGUCCAAAAGCCAGCUCUAUUCGGACUUACACACCCCUGGGAGGUAUGGCAGGGUGAUCCUCCUCUCCCCAACCGGGGACAAUAUUUUGCUCCAGGCUGAGGGGAUCCUGCAGACCCACCGAGCCGUGCUGGAAAUGAAGGAUGGGAGGAACAGUUUUAUUGGACACCAACUGGGCGGGGUAGUGGAAGUGCCAAACAGCAAAGAUCAGCGGGUCAAGUCAGCCAGAGCCAUUCAAAUCACCUACUACCUCCAGACCUAUGGCUCUGCCACCCAAGACCUCAUAGGGGAGAAGUGGGAGAAUGAGUUCUGUAAGCUUAUAAGGAAGCUCCAGGAGGAGCAUCAAGAACUCCAGCUCUACUCUUUAGCAUCCUUUAGCCUCUGGAGGGACUUUCAUAAGACCAGCAUCCUGGCCAGAAGCAAGGUCCUGGUGAGCCUCGUGCUGAUCCUGACCACAGCCACCCUCUCCAGCUCCAUGAAGGACUGCUUGCGCAGUAAGCCCUUCCUGGGCCUCCUGGGGGUGCUCACAGUAUGCAUCUCCAUCAUCACAGCAGCAGGGAUCUUCUUCAUCACCGAUGGAAAGUACAACUCCACCCUGCUGGGAAUCCCGUUCUUCGCCAUGGGUCAUGGAACUAAAGGAGUGUUUGAGCUUCUGUCCGGAUGGCGGAGAACCAAAGAGAACUUGCCCUUCAAAGACAGGAUAGCAGAUGCCUAUUCUGAUGUGAUGGUCACCUAUACCAUGACCAGCUCCCUGUACUUCAUCACUUUUGGCAUGGGUGCCAGCCCAUUCACAAACAUAGAGGCUGUGAAGGUCUUCUGUCAAAACAUGUGUGUCUCUAUUCUGUUGAACUACUUCUACAUUUUCUCCUUCUUUGGCUCCUGUCUGGUCUUUGCUGGCCAACUAGAGCAAAACCGCUACCACAGCAUCUUUUGCUGUAAGAUCCCUUCUGCAGAAUACCUGGAUCGCAAACCUGUGUGGUUCCAGACAGUGAUGAGUGAUGGGCAUCAACAGACGUCCCAUCAUGAGACGAACCCCUACCAGCACCACUUCAUUCAGCACUUCCUCCGUGAACAUUAUAAUGAAUGGAUUACCAAUAUAUAUGUGAAGCCAUUUGUUGUCAUCCUCUAUCUCAUUUAUGCCUCCUUCUCCUUCAUGGGGUGCUUACAGAUCAGUGACGGAGCCAACAUCAUCAAUCUACUAGCCAGUGAUUCGCCAAGUGUUUCCUAUGCCAUGGUUCAGCAGAAAUAUUUCAGCAACUAUAGCCCUGUGAUAGGAUUCUACGUCUAUGAGCCCCUAGAGUACUGGAACAGCAGCGUCCAGGAUGACCUAAGAAGACUCUGUAGUGGAUUCACUGCAGUGUCCUGGGUGGAGCAGUACUACCAGUUCCUGAAAGUCAGCAACGUCAGUGCCAAUAACAAAAGUGACUUCAUCAGUGUCCUGCAAAGCUCAUUUUUAAAAAAGCCAGAAUUCCAGCAUUUUCGAAAUGAUAUCAUCUUCUCCAAGGCAGGGGAUGAAAGCAAUAUCAUUGCUUCUCGCUUGUAUCUGGUGGCCAGGACUAGCAGAGACAAGCAGAAAGAAAUCACAGAAGUGUUGGAAAAGCUGAGGCCCCUAUCCCUCUCAAAGAGCAUCCGAUUCAUCGUGUUCAACCCCUCCUUUGUCUUCAUGGACCAUUACAGCUUGUCUGUCACAGUGCCUGUUCUGAUUGCAGGCUUUGGUGUUCUCCUGGUGUUAAUCCUGACUUUUUUCCUAGUGAUCCACCCUCUGGGAAACUUCUGGCUAAUUCUUAGCGUCACCUCAAUUGAGCUGGGCGUUCUGGGCUUAAUGACAUUAUGGAACGUCGACAUGGAUUGCAUUUCUAUCUUGUGCCUUAUCUACACCUUGAAUUUCGCCAUUGACCACUGUGCACCACUGCUUUUCACAUUUGUAUUAGCAACUGAGCACACCCGAACACAAUGUAUAAAAAGCUCCUUGCAAGACCAUGGGACAGCCAUUUUGCAAAAUGUUACUUCUUUUCUUAUUGGGUUAGUCCCCCUUCUAUUUGUGCCUUCGAACCUGACCUUCACACUGUUCAAAUGCUUGCUGCUCACUGGGGGUUGCACACUUCUGCACUGUUUUGUUAUUUUACCUGUGUUCCUAACGUUUUUCCCCCCUUCCAAAAAGCACCACAAGAAAAAGAAACGUGCCAAGCGAAAGGAGAGAGAGGAAAUUGAAUGCAUAGAAAUUCAAGAGAACCCGGAUCACGUCACCACAGUAUGAGGGGUAUAGACCAGUGGAUUAUUUUUCUUUUCCAGUAUUGCACAAUGAUGCAGGGCAAGUAAAGCUCAGACCUCAGCUGCUUGGGCUGGCCAGGGGUAACAAGGCAAGUCAGAUCAAGAGUGCAUUAUUCAUGACACUUCAAGGUGCCUGCUUCUUGGGGGGAAGAGGGAAUAAAAAAAGAGGAAAAAGUUAUUUGCAACCUUGUUCUCCUCUAAAAACAAGUUUCUGGAUGUAAUCUGAGAGCUCUUCCAAGGAAUGGAUGAAUCAAUGGAGUGUUAAGAUAGAAGGCCAAAAUAACCAGCUUCUUUUAAAAAUAAAAUGCUUAGGAGUGAUGGAGAAGCAAGGAAAGGUGUCCUUCAAAUAGGGGGAAAGACAUGGGAAAUGUGCCAUGGCACUUUUCAUGCUUGUUUUUUGAACAGGUUGGUCAAAGGAAACCUAUGCACUUGGGAAGUACAUAUUUAAUACUGUCUAAACCAAAGGACUUCCCAAUCCAUUUUAUGUGUACAUAUAUAUGUAUAUAUCCCGUAUAUACAUAUACUUAGUUUUGUCUUUAGGGUACAUUGACGUUUAUGUGGAGGGAGCUGUCCAUUUGAAGAUAGGCUGGCUUUUCCCUAGAAAGUCAAAUCAACCUUAGCCAAAUUUAUAGAUUCAUUAAUAGCCGUUCUAAAUCAACCCAAGUGUCUCAGCAGUCAGUGUGUCAUUCAACUGUGGGAUGAGCAAAAUAAACAGAGAUGUGAGUUCAUUAGAUUAUGCAUAUCAUGUCAGCAGUCAUCUAGACUUUUGCUUUGGAUGACUUCACAAGAAAACACAAAAGGCAUUUGAAUUAAUUACCACAUGGACAAGGUUUACUGUUUCAUAUUAGAAAUAAACAGUUGAUAUGGAUUUUCGUUGGCUUUUACUGUAUUUGGAAGACUGAUAUGGCUGCUUUCAGUGAGCUCACCCAAUUGCAAAUGAGCGCUUUACACAGAUUAUCCAUACAUGAGUCUAAGGGUGCACAAGUAUGUGUAUGUGAGUUGGGGUACUCCAUAGUUACACCGUUCUUAUUUUAGAUAGGGAAAAUAACUGUCAUGGAAUAUAGAUAAUUAACAUAGGAGAAAGGAGACAUAACUAGGAAACUCGUAGAGUGAAAUAGAAUAAAAUGGACCAUACCCACUCAUCACAUGCCAUCUACUAGUUCUUAGCAUAAGGAAACUAUUCUAAUCCUAUAAACUCUAGUGUAUUCCUUGCAUUAGUAUUUGGAACAUAACCCAGGCCAUGAUCACUAUAGUAGUGUUCACUACACCUACUGCAGUACCAUUUGUAGCUUCUCACAAUAGUGUUGCUCUUGUUACCUGGAAAGUGCUCCUCGGUUGGCCCACCUCCUAGGGUGAUCGCAGCUCUCCACAGGUGGGAUAUUAACUAUAACUGCUGCUGAAUUCUUUCUCAAACAAAAGUACUGAGGUAAAUGUUUUCAUUAAGUUAAAGUUUAAAACUACUCCCAAGCACCUGUUGGGUGCUUACUUGGACUAUUGCUGUGCCUCCUGUCACAGGAAAUUACUAGAAAAUGCCUUUUCCCAUGCCAAGCAGUAACAUAAUUUAUUUCCAGGUAGGACAGAAUAAAUGUCCGAUGAUUAUAAAAUCUGCUAGUAAGCUCUUUUACCUAGAAGAAAGCUACUACUUCCCAUCAACUUUGGUUCUAUGUUUUAAUCAAAUUAAUAAUACCUAAAAUAACAAAACUCCUUGACUCAAUUAUGUUCAGAAAAAAGGUACAAACCAUUCCAUUCUCGUUAUAGUCUCUGGAAAUGAAGUUGAUAGACUAAUGAAGUAACAAAACAAGUAUACUUAGACAUAUAACUUUCCAGAAUAUAAAGGGGAAAGGGAACAGACCCUAAAAUGAAAACAUUUAAGUAAUAUUUCAUUUAUUAAAUGGAGUUUGUUUUGUUUUACCUUGAGGUAAUUGGGUUUCAACAGGAAAUGAUCUAUGUCUUCUCCAUUGUGUCAGUUUCAGUGCAAUAUCUAUAGAUUUGAGUGGGGAAAAUUAUUGCCCAUAAUCAUAGGGUUAUUGUUUUUACAUUAUUUGUAAAGUCAUGUCACAAAUACUCCUAGCCUUUUGCCUCAUGAACUGCUGUACUAGAAUGAACUGGUAUUUGGUACGAGUAGCCUCCAGACCAUGAUCUCAUAUCUGAAGUAGAAGUUUCAGAGGAGGUUUUUGGUUGGGUUUUGAUUUUUUGUUUGGGUGGGAGUUUUGUAGUGGGGGUGCAGGGAGGAGGAGAAUUCCUCUUACAGAUUACCCAUCAUUUGUAAAGAUUUGAUAUGGAAGAUUUUUAUCUCCCAUAUCAAAAUAUGGGAGAUAAUCACUGAGAAAGUUAAUUAACUAUCACUCCUUUUCUUCCCAUUGUGUGCCAUGCUCCACUCAUUCACCUAUUUUUUAAAAGAUUGGCUAUUGGGGUUGGUUUUUUCUUGGUUCCUAUAGACCAUUCUGCAUGCAAAGAAGAAUGGCAGGCUGAUUUACAGGGAAAGAAUCAAGCAUGCCAGUUGUCAAAAGCACAUGGAGGAAAUGGUAUACACUGCCAAAUGACCAGGGCAGAUCUAAUAUUAUGUCUCCAUCCAGAUAGUCUCUGUUUAGAUAGGGAAAAACAGUUCUUUUUUAGUUUAUGUCUUCAAGGAUCAAAGUGUCUAAGAUAAAUAUGAAUUUCUCAUUGUUCGAGUGACUAGAGGGCAUUUUGGAAGGAACAUUAUCUUUUCCAGGACACCGUAGUACUCUUUAGAGAACUGUAGCAAUAAUUUACUGAAAUGGAAUUAUUUGUUCUGGAAGAGUUAAUAUACCACCUAAAGUGUCUUAAUGCAGUCCUAGGAAGUAAUUUAAUCCUAAGAAGAAUCUAACAGAGCAUCGUCUGACCUCCCAACCUCACUGUGAAACAGAUGUUUCCAAGAAUUCCAUUUCCUGAAUACUAAGAUACAUCCUAAGAUAUGAGAUCAUGACUUGCAGGUCACCCCCAAUCCCAACCUUUUUUGGUAGCUUGUAUGCACCUCUCCCUAGUUUUUCCAGUUUGCACUCAUUGUUUUGUUCAUUUAUGAAGUACUAAUGCCAUUCAAAUUAGGAACUUAUCUGUUGUCAGCAGAUGACCAAUCAACUCCUAGAAGAGAAGAAAUUUGUGGGAAAUAUGUUAGCUUUGUGUAAUAUUUUAUUUAAUUGAAACAUAUAUGCCCUUAAAGUAAGAGGUUAUAAAGUUUGAAAAAACUACUCUUUUUCUGUAUGUAAACUGGAAUGUGGAUUUAUUUCCUUCCAUCAGAAUUUAAAUUUGAAUUGGAAAGUGCCAUGUGAGCUCCACUCUCUUUGAUGUUAAUAAACUUCAAAGAGGUACUCACCUAAAUUACAGAGAGAUCAGCUAAAAGAUUUUUUACCGUUUAUGGUUAAAGGUAAUCAUACCUUAGAGAUUUGAUUCUUUAGACCAGCCUUAAUUCUUUUUAAUGAAAGUCAUGUUUAGAUGUCUUCCCAGGAAUUCUUGCAGUUACUAUGAACCUCUUUGAAGGCUGUGCAUGAGUAUUCUAUGAAAGAACUAUUCUCCUCUGUUGUUGUAUCAUGUAAGUGGCCCUUUCCUAUUUGAUUCCCAUUUAUUUCCACAGAAUUUAGGUUUUUACCUUGUGAGGUGAGAAGAAUAAUGAUGACAAAUGUUUUAUGAUGCUAUUAUAGUUAUUCUUGAAUGUUAAAUUCAAGACAGUAAAAGCUUUGUCCAUUUUGUAAUUAUCUAUCACAUUUCCCCGUAAUAAGCUAAUCCUUCUAGGCUUGUGGUUAGAGCUAAGGAUUAACUAUUGCCAUUCAGAAUUACAUGUAUUUUUAUAAGUUGACUGUAAAUAUCAUAAUUACAGUCACAUAUUUUUAUGACCAAAUAGUUAUGAAUGCACGGCACUAUGCAUGCUUUGUUAUUAAUAGUACAUAGGUUAUUAAAGACACUAUUUUCAGGGUUAUUGCAACUUUUAUUAAAAUUUCUUACAUCACCUAUUCAUAAAUGCCUCAUGGCUUUUGGUCUUAAGGGCCUAAAGUCCACAGAAAGUUCCAUCCCCAGGUAAGCAAUUUAAGAAUUGCCUUCCCUGGGUAUCAGUAACAACCACCUCUUCUAGAAUGGACUUCGGAAAAUCUCAGAAGUGAAAUCUGGCUUCCAGGCAAAGGGCCUAGUAUAUUCUGUAUUGGUUAGUAAAUAAACAUAAUUUUAUGUCUUGUGUUUGCUAAUCUUAUGGUGAAGCAGAAAAUACAAUGCCAUGAGACUGACAUUUAGAUAUUGUCUCUUAGAGAUUGGAGAAGUCAAUGAUUUGCUCGGCAUCCUACUACAGGGAUCUUUCUGUUCAGUCUGGUUUGUUGGUGUCUGCGAAGGAUAUUGGCAAUCUUUGCAAAAGUGAAUCUGAAAACUGUUACUUAUUCCAAAAGAGCCUCAGAAGCACUUUUCUUCCCUUUACAAACAAAAAACAAACAAAAAAAGUUUUAGCUUUUUCUCAAUUACCAAAAUUUUGUGACAAUUUUAUGACAUUGACCCAAAACAUAUUUAUGGCUGAAUUGGUAUGCCCUUGCUAUUUCCCCAUCUUCAAUCUCAAUAUGAAAUUGAACAUCAUCACUGUGGUGCGGACCUUUAUGCUAAUAUUUUAAAUCAGUGAGCUGCAGAUAUAUAGGAUAGGGAAAAAUCAAGUUUUUUACUACUUUGUCUACAAAAUAACUACAAUGAUAUUGACCCAAAUGAAAGCAGCAAAAUCAUAAGUGAAAGCAACAAAGCCACACUGCAUGAGAUCCAGCAGGGGAGGGACUGUGUAUGGGUAUAGCAGCAGUAAAUUACCUUGAUUUAUCAACUAAAGGACCAAGAUUAAUCCACCAUCACGUUUAACUUAGGAGCACAAGAGGUGGUGUUCUGUGUUUGAAGUGUUGUGGAGUUAGAUCAGGCAACAUUUGAAAUGACACUGGAAGGAUAUUGAGAGAUGAGCCCACAUCUCAGAAAUCAAGAUGUCUGUAAGUAGGUGUGAUAGAACAAGUGGAAUAAUACCACAUAUUCUGUGAUUUAGAAUACAGCAGAGAGAAUCACGUGGUGUUGCAAAACUAUAGAUUCUCAACUGCUAGCAAACUUGAUCAUAGGCAAAUACAUUGCACUUGAAGACUGGGUUCUCAUUUGUUAGAUUCAUAACCUAAUCUUUGCAGUGGGAGGUGCUCCUGAAUUUCCAAGCACAAAGGAAGAGCCGUAGACCCUUUUGUUAGUGAAAGUGAAAAGCUAGGGAGACUCUUUGUAAAGAAGCUUAAAGUAAGCACCGACAUAAGCAUCAUUCAUUCCCAGAGUGGCUCUCAUUGACUAUAUUUUGUGAGUCUUUGAGUCAUAAUGAACACUUUUUCUAAUCAGUUUUUUUCAUACUUAAUGAGGACUCUCUAUUGCUGAUAGAGAAGCCACUUGCUUUUCUUAUAAAACGGAAAACAACUCAAAAGAGCAAUAUAUAGGGUUAAGAAUAUAUUUAUAGUAUAACUUCCUAGUCUACAAAUCACAUUUUAUGUCUUCUGCAUCUCUAAAGAUGUAAAAAUUAAAUGGGAGUGUACCUUAAACUGAAAACCUCUAUAAGGUAGAUAUUUUUAAUAUAAUAAAGUAUUUAUAAAGGAAACUAUCACUGAUUUUGCACUAUCUUAAAUUAUAGAAAGCCAGCUUCUACUAUUUUUCCCCAGUUGAAAAUUUCCCUUAAGAAAGGUCUCACAGGUCAUGGUAAUUAUAAAAUCUUAAAAAUCAGAAAGAAACUUUAGGAACAGAGUAGGAAUCACCACUGAUGGUGUGUGAUUCCUGCUGUGUAUGAUUUCAUUGCACUUAUCUGAGCUGAGGUUUUUAGAAGCCAUUUGUAGCUGAGCUCUGGUUUCCCAACAGCUAAUGGCAUGGUCUAAUAGAGGAGCAUUACGGUUUUCUUUCCCUCUGUUGCCACAGUUUGUAGAGUAAGCACAUUGCCCACAAGGCUCUGUCAAACCAGAGGGGGAAAAAAAUUCUAAUGCUUUGGAAGACUGCAUUGAAGAAUUUCCUAGGAAUAACUAGGAAACACUCUCAUGGACGAAAGAUUACUGGUGUUUAAUAAAAAUGUAUAACUUUUCAGUGCUAUAUAAAUUUAACUUAUAUUCUCAGUAGCGGCAGUCUACAGUAUGUUAUGGGGAGCAUUUAAAUUAUCUAAUGUAAUAUGGUUACUAGAAUCUCUCCCUGGACACGGAAACACCUUCUAUCAUUUUAUCUGAUGAAUUCACUGGUUGUUGGUAGCAACACUGAUAGAGCUGGGGAAAAAAAAAAAAGAAUAAGCCGUCAUAUUCUUGCAUCUCCUGGUACAGUCUGUAGCAUCUAUUUUCAAGUAGAAUAAGGGAAUUCUGGCAUCUUUUCUUCACAAACAUAAAUGUGCUACAAACUGAUAAACUAGACCUUAAACUAGUCAAUGCAAAUAUCCCAAAGUUUUAGUAGUUUAAGCAACAACUUUAUUAUACUUUCCUGUUAAUUAUGCAUAUUUUUCAGCAGUAGACUUUUUUGCUCUGAACUAGGAAAUCUGUCACAGAUUGAAAAGGGCAGAGAUCUCUCCAAGCUACCUCAUAAGGGUAUUUAAAGACAAAAUGGCAUGCAAUCUUUGAUUAAAUGGCAAUAUAUUAAAGCCACAAAGCAAUAUUAUUUAUCACCUUUCCUUGAUGCUCAUUCACUUUAUCAAAUUAGACAAGGCAAAAUGUAAAAUGAGCACUCCUAUAUGCAGUCCCACUUAUACAUUCUGGUUAACAUAAUAUUCAUUAAUAUGAAAUCUUUCAAGGCAGUUGUUAGUUGUCUCCCUACAGAUAUCCCAGAGCUCAAAAAUUGACUCAGAAAGAGAGUAAUCUGACUUUGAUUAGAGGCAGCAGUCUACCCAGUAAGAUGCACAAAUAAUCUGUGAAUAACUUCAGAAAAAUUCCAAGUGCAUUUCACUUAUCACUUUUCUUGGAGGAAAAAAUCUGUUCGGGUGUUUGUUUGUUUAUUCUAGGCAAAUAGAAAGAGACAAAGUUACCAUUAUUUGGCAUUUUACUUAAGUUUUCUUUUCCUCUGGAAGGCAUUGCUAUUAUUUUCUGCUAAAUCGGGGUUUUUAAAACACAAGUCACUUACGGAAACAUUAGCAUCAGUGAAAAGAAAACUCCUAGGGAGAAACAGUCUUCACCCAUGCAUAGACAAAUUGUAGAAAUGAGAGUAAAAGUUGAGCAUUUUUAUUUUCUUUCCUAAAACAAAACCCACUUGUUCUUAAUCCUAGCUAGACAAAAUACCAGUUUCUACAGCAAAGAAGGGUGACUAAAUGUAUGAAAUUAUGAAACUUUGAUGUAUUAACACUACAAACCUCAUGGCAAACCAUCAAUUCCAGAUGUCUUUACCCAUAACAAUAUUCCUUCUAAAAUACUCUAUUACAUAUAGGUUCAUCCCAUUCAUGAAAACAGCCUCAUUUAUCACUCCCAAAAUAGUACAAACAAAGCCAUUUUAGGUUUCUGCUCUGUAGUUCUGUACCUUGGGCUCUACAACUAAAGCUACCUUACUGAGGAAAGCUUAAAAACGAAUUGUGAACAAAAAUGUCAAAUCAAAAAAACAUUACCCAAGUUGUAUUUCCAUCCAAAAAUAUCUCCUGUGAAAUAGAAGACUGCUGUGUAGCCAUUUUAGAUCUCACAAAGAAGAAAAUAUUCUAAAAGUACCUAUUUUUGAUCUUACUAAGAACCCAAACCAAAAGUCCUUCCAAAGUUUCCAAAGUUUCCAAUUCACCUGAAUUUGGUCCAUUAUCAAAAUUUACCUCUAUGUUGAUCAGUGAAAAAACAUUUUGCAAAACAGGUUUUUCUUAACUAUAAUAGAAACAAAUAAAGAACAAAUUAUUUCCCAUAGAUUUGCAUGUGUAAACACACAUUUAAUAAUUAAAUGAAUCUCAUACCUCAGUCAAGGGAAAUUAUGUUCCAAAUAUUUCCUUGUUCGGUUCAUCAUUAUUUUCAUGUUUUGGACACACUGAAAUACAAUAAUUUUAGUUAAAUUGCUCAUAAUUUAUCUGCAUGACAAAUCUAUUAUCUAAAGCUUACAGGUACAAAUCUUAAGAAAAAUAACAAUUAAAUCUUAGCUACUUGGAAAAAAAAGUCAUCAAAAUCAUAUUUACUACAGUGCCACUAGGCAAAGUUAAACAGCAUUUCUGGCUAUCUCAACUUUUUAUUUUAACAACAAAAGAAAUCUAGUUCCAUUAGUCAUAAUAAUAGAAAUAAUUUAUAUAUUAAAGUAGUGAUAAAUUAUACAGGUGUAUAUUCUAUAGUUCUUAGGGUCAAAUAUGAGGUCUUUUAAAAUCACAAUCACAAAUGCUGUAAAAGCUAGGUUAUUCUUAAAUUCGCCAGAUUUUUCUUCAUUCUUUAUUGUUAGUAUUAAAUGCCCCACAGAAUAUUAUAAUAUGCAACUUAUUCCUCUAACCUCAGUGAGAACUUCGAGCAUGCUACCUUUUAAUUCUAGGCUAAGAAUUAAACUUCCUAAACAAAACAUCUUAUAACAUCACAAUGUAAAAUAACAUAAUCUAUGUUUUUUUAGUAUUUUAUUGAAUCACAAGUUCUAAAACUUAUAAUGUAAUUUUUUAUCCUUUAAACAUUCAAGAAUACAUACAUUAAAAUAAUACUGUGAUGAUAUAUAUCAAUUAUCUCUCCGUGGUUAAGAUAAAGCAUUCUGAAGCAAAUACAAAAUGUCUUGGCAUUCCUGAGAGAUAUUUUUAUGAAUCCCUAAGUUCACAAAUGUCUCUAAAACACAUAAAUUACUAAAGCAUUACUAAAAGAUUCAGAUAGCACUUUAACACCCCUUAAUAAUUAUGUUACCUUCAAAUCUACAGCAAUUUAUAAUCGGGUCAAAUAAAUUCUACCUAAAAUUUAUCACUGCAUUACAUUGCAUUAUUGUAGUAAUAUUAACUAUAAAAAUACUUGAACCAACAUUUUUCUCACCAUAUGAGAGCUGCAGAAGAUGGAGACAAUGAGUGAGCCAGCGGCUCCUCAGUAGUACCCAGAGAUUAAUCACAAAGCACAUCCCUUUGGCUGCACGCUAUACAGUUUCAAGCUGGGGCAUAAUUGUUCAGGGGCUAUCAGCACCACUUCUAAGUCACUAAAACCAAUCAUGUUAAAUAUUUCAAUAUCCAAGUCCACUGUAUUUUGAUGAAUAAUGUGGUGGCAUUAUACAUAACGCAUAGAUAACCAACAUUCAAAAUAUGUAAGGUCACUUGAUGCCAAAAUUAUACUUAAACAAUUUAAUAUUCCACAAGCCACUUCAAAAGCUUUAUCAUUGCAAAGCUCUCCUCAUUAUUGACGUAUGAUGAGGAGACCAAAGAAGUCUUAGUAAUAUUUCAUUUUAUAUAGUUUGCCGUAUGUUUUCUUAAAAACAAGGAUGCCUUUAUGUCUUUCCUGGAAAUGUUUGGACUUAUUCAAUAGCCAUUUUCCUGUCCAAAUUUAGUAUUUUAAUUAUUAAUUUUAUUCUGCUUUUUUCCUUUAAAUAUGUUCAACUUUUAUCAUUUCUAAAAUAACUUUUCUUUAGAGUAAUUAAGCAUGUUUUCUCCUUUACAUAAAAAUAAGCAUGGCUAGAAAGGAAUGAAAUAAGAACUCAGAAAAAUUAAGCUGGACAUUUGGAACCUAUUUGCAAAUACUAAAUAAAGUUUGCAAAAGUACUAUUUAUUGUCAUUUAUAUGUGCUUCAAGUUGAAAUUCUCCACUGAUUUUAUUUUAAAAAUGGCAACUGACAUGCCAAACUAUGAAGCACACAAUGUCUGCUUUGCAGACGUUCAGUAAUUAUCCAUUCAGUGAAGAAAAAUAUAAAAGACUUCUCCAGCUUAUCAGUUGCCUGCUCAUGACCUAAUGAAAAGGAGGUUAUUUAAUAAUUUCAAUCUUUGAGAGCCCAUAUUCAGAAGCUUUUGUUGUUGUUUUGUUUCAUUUUCUUGAAUUUUCCUAUAUAGCCAGUUACACAAUAAUAAGGCCCCAUAUAAAGGAAGAAUUUCAAGUUUGUUGGUAAUAACUGUCCUUUCCUAUAAGUUGAAAUGCUACAACCUAGAGCUAUACACAUCUUGAUAGUAAAAUAAGGGAGAAUGUGAUCCAACAUAAAGAAAAAUUAAGGACAAGGGUGUUUUUUUAAAAAAAAAGGUAAAGUGAGAAAAAAUUUUAAAACGGAUCUAAAACUGUUGAAGAAGGGACUAAACAACUGAACUGAAACCUUUUUUUUAUUUAGUUUCUGUUCAUUAGCUUAGUUAGGCUUUAAAAACAAAGGAACACAUUGGAAAGUUUCAGAAAAACCCUGACAUAUCUAAGUCUCCAAAAAGUUUGUUACUCUUUAAAAAGAUAGAACUAGAAAUUCAGUCCCAUUUUAGGAUCAAGAUUUGAUGUAGAUGGGUUUCUGAAGUACCCCUAGAUGGCUUGUGAUUGUACCUAUUUACUUACCUCAUAUUUAGGAGCACCUAUAUUGGUCUCUGUGCUAGGCUCAGAAGAAAAUACCACUAAACUAUUCAUAGUUCCUGACUUUGAGGUAUGCAUGAUCUGUUGAGGAAAUUUGCAGCUGGAGUAUUCAAGGAAAGUAAGGAAGGAAUUAUGAACUGAUCCACAUUGAAGUGUGGGUAAGAUUCUAAUAGAUAGAGAUGGAGGAUGGGCUCAACAGUCAGGGAGAAAAAGUGAAAUAUACAAGGGCAGGAAAGCAGGUUGUCCAGGAUGAAGGCUAUAACAGAUGAGAUGAUAGCAACCCAGAAGAGACUUGUUACAGAUGGGAAUAAAAAGGAAGCGCCCAUUGUGAGUGGUAUUAUAAAGCAUUGCCAGGAUAUGGGGAGUUACUUGGAUUUUGGAGAGGGAUCAUAAAGAAAAAGCUCUUUUUAUGAUGUAUCCUUGGGCUUAAAUGCAGUGAAUGGUUUACAAAAUGUAAAUACACAGUCUCUAUUUUUGAAUUUUAACUGUUAAAAUCAAGGAUCCCAAAACUGAGCAAUAUCACAUAAAUUUAUAAUCUCUCUUGCUUUGAAAUGUAGUGGUUGCAAGAGCCAGUUUAGAGCAUGAGUUUGAUUCUCCUGAUGAUGGAACACCGUCCACGUUCUGGCACAAAAGCCCUCAAAGUGUGAGAGUAAGAGACUGACAUGGAUUGCUGGGAACCCAAACUCUCCAGAACAAACAGCUCAAACUAAUACACUCCAAUUAACUAUCUCUGUUAAUAUUAUUUUAAUUAACAAUUCAAAUAAUACCUGCCUAAUAGAAUAGGUAUUAUUGUCCCUGAUUUAUAGAUUGUUCCCAGAAAGAAAACAUUGUAAACAAGUACUAUGUCCCUAUGGUAAAAUAUAUCAUCUUUUCAUCAUAAAUCAGUAUGAAAGGUGCAUGUACAGAGAAGUCCAAAUGUAAAUUAUAUGUGAUGAAAAAUAACUGCAUAGAUUUUCUCCCCAUCUAUCCUUUUCUAAAUGUAAAUUUUAAGACAAUGAGUUUGUUAAAAUGCUUAAAACUAUUUUUUAAAUUCACUUCCUUAUGAUUCACUGAUGCUUUCUUUGAAGAUCACAUAAGGUACAUAUGCACUUAGUUUUUAAGCAUAAACCUAACUGAUUUAUACAUUACCCUUGUCCUUUUUAAUAGUUAAAGUUUUAAUUAUAAUAGUGGUGCUCCCCAAAACCAGCAAUCAUAUUACAAGAUGUUUGGAGGAAUAUAUUUUAAACUUUAAACCUGAAAAAAGCAUUUCCUAAUUAUGCUUUUUAGAGUUAUAGAUAAGGUUGGAGUUGGCCUGGGGAGGCCCCAUUUUCCAACUGGUUCACGAGGAGGACAUCUGUUCACAGAAGUAGAAUGGAGAUAAAUCCAACAACCAAGUGGCCAUACGAGACCAUGGUCAACAAACACACUCUAAGAGACAUUUUGGAUAACCCUAGGAGUAACAAAGCUAGUGGUUCUCAAAAUUUGCUGUACUUUGGAAUGACCUAGAGAGAUGUUUAAAGUCUCAAUGCCCAGACUUCAUGCCAGACUACUUAAAUCAAUAUAUCCUAUAGCGAGACCCAACCUCAGUACUUCUGGGAGUUCCCAUAGUGAUUUCAAUGUGUGGCUCAAUUUGAAAAACAGUGGCUUAGACAACCAAGUCAACACAUUUAAUCCAAUAAAUACUGAUAGAGCCUUUUAUUAAGUGAAGUUUUAAAAAGUCACAAGACAAAAGCGUCUGUGACAUCUAUAACUAGAAUAUAAGCCAGAACUUGUACAGAGUCCAAAAGGAGAUAUCCAGAGGGUAGAGAGAUGAUUUCUAGUAGAGCCAAACCUGGUAUGAGUGUGUUGCAUUAAGAUAGCACUUAAGAUGAGGUAAGAUUAUUGGCCUGAGCACCCCAUGUGACGGGACCAGACUGAGCAAAGCCAUAACAUGCAACAAAAGCACAGAAUAUGUUCCUGGGUCAACGAACUCAAUUUAGCUUGAGGGUACAUUUCCAGUACAGGAGUUGAAUUUGUACAAACCAGAAAGUUUCAUAUAAGGACCUGCAAACAUCAUGCUGCAGAAUUUAUAUUUGAUUUGAUGGACUCAGAUUACUUUUUAUUAUUAUUAUUAUUAGAUUCAAAAUUUAGAAGUAUUAAUCUGCAAUGUUCUAAGUGUAGGUUAGACUGGAGAUGAGAGACCUGAACCAAAGAAUUAAGUUAGGAGGCUGUUGUGGUCAUCAGCAAUGAAGGUAAUAUUGGCCUGAAAUAGAGUUGUGGCACUGAAUAUAAAAAGGAAGAAAUAAAUACAAUUCACAAAACUUAUAUCUGUAAGAUGGCCUGAACACCCAAGAACUUUGAGUGUCUAAAACACAACAAUAUUCACAUUAGUGAAUUUAAUGUGGUAUAACAGUAACUAGUUAUUAGCUCUGUGUGAUCUAUUUACUACAAUACUCUAAUGUAUAGUUUAAUCUUCACAUUCCUGUGGUUUUGACAUGCAGCGUGGCCCAUUUUUAUAACAUUUGUAAAGCUUUACCACAAAUUUUCAGGAAAUUGCUUUAUCUUUACAGAACAGUUGAUUUGGUUUUCUGCAUAUCUAACUUGGGGAAAAAUGGUUUAUAUUGCAUUAAUUAAAUUCAGUAAAUAAAAGAUGAGUCAAAGAGGAAGAAACGAAUAUCUUAGGAACAUAAAUAGGCAGUCUAAUCUUUUAUACUUUUUUCCAUGUAAAAUUACUGGAUACUCAGGUAUAUAUAACUCUUAUCUACAUGCACGUAUUAUAGCUAGAGACACUACAAUAGUAUCUAGAUUAAUCUACAUAUAUAAACAUCAAUUUAAUUAGCAAAUAAUUCUUGAGAUUUAUUUGCAUUUCAGGGAAUUUAGCAGUUCAGGUGAUUUAUGCUUAGAAACAAGAUCACUGUUCCUCCCACAAUCAGAGAUCUGCUCUGCAGUCAUCUUCUAUGAAAGUUAUGUAUAAGGCACAUGCUUUUAUUCUACCAUAAAGAUGUAGUAUUGCAAUGUUAUGUCAGCACUGGACAAAGAUGGAUAUAUAUGUAAAAUGUAAUUUUCACAACAUAUCCUUACACAUAGUUACACAUUCAUUGGAUGGCCUGUCUCUAAUUCAAAACUUUUCCUAUGGUAUAAUUGUCCUGUCAAAUAUUUCACACAUACAUGGUUUUAACAUUAGCAUUAAAAUGACCUGUGAAAAUAAUCCAUAUGAACUCUUUGUAUUCUUCUACAGUCAUAGAACUAAAAUACGUGAGGAUGAGGAAGCAGAUAACAACUUGAGAAAAUGUAAAAGAGUUGGAACUUGGAGCCACAGUGCCAUGCAAUGGGGCCACACAGCAGCUUGAUCAUCCACGUAGCUUUAUGCGAUGCCCUUUGGGUCAUGGCUUUCACCAGGUAGCUUACUCAAAAAAAAUGUAAUUAUCUAUUAACCCCUUUAUUCUCCAAAUCUUUCAUUCAAGAAGAAUUUUAAACAUCUUCUAUGUGCCAGACACAUAGAGAGUAAAUGCAAAGAGAAAUGAGAGGCAGCCACUACCCAUCAAGGAUUUUAGCAAAGCAAACUAGUAGGUGAAAUAGCCAUAUAUAUAUAUGUGUGUGUGUGUGUAUAUAUAUAUCUCAAAAAUAAUGGGCUCCAUUUAUAGAGCAGCGAUUCUCCCACUUAAGCAUGUAUCAAAAUCACCUGGAGGGCUUGUCAAAGCACAGCCUGCAUAUCCCCAUCUCCAGAGGUUCUGAUUCAAUAGAUCUGGAGUGAGGCCUGAAAAUUUACAUUUCUAACAAGUUUUCAGGUGAUGCUAAUGCUACUAGUCUGAGGAACCACACUUGGACUUUGAAAAUCUCUGAAAUCUAAGUUUGUGAACAGCAACAGACAUUCUGAGAAUAGUUGGAUUAAAUCUGUCCAGGGAAGAAGGUGAGGACAAAGGUCAGCUUCUCACCACUAGGCCUGAAAGGCUGCAUAGUUGAAGAGUGCAAAGACAUUCCAGUUUGAAGAAAAGAAAUUACCUGAACUAAGGCCAUAUCUGACAAGUCUACCUGUUGGUAGAACUCAUCUAGAAGACUUUUUAAACUCUUGAAGGGAUGGCCUUAGUAAUCUCUAUUUGUAAUAAGUUGCUCUGGACAGUCUUUUCAUGAAGAAAAUUUAGGAACAUGGAACCAAGGCGUAGAGUAUAAAAGAAUGUGUCAUUUUCAGAGAAGUCCUGUUAUAGACUGGUUUAACUAGAACCACUGUAUACUAGAACUAGCACUCUAUACUAGAACUAGAUUCAUGUAGGACAUGAGUUAAGUUUGAAUUUCCAAUAAUCAGUGAAUGAAAUUUUUAGUACAAGUAUGUUUCAUGCAAUAUUUGGAAUCUACUAUACUAAAAAUACUUGUUUCUCUGAAAUUCAAAUUUAACUGGGCAUAUUGCAUUUUUACUUGCUAAAUCUCACAACCCUAAGAAUGUAGGGUAUGUGUCAGGUGGAGAAAAGAACCAGAAAUAAUGAGGCUGAAACACUAUUAUAUUAUUAGGCCAAAUAAUAGUAAAGUACUAUUUUUCAUGUGGGAUAUGCAAGUGUAGCAUGUAGCUAAUGAAGCUUAAAUUUCUGAGCCCAUUGCUUACAUAAGUCUUUUGGAGGCCCUAGGACAGUCCUUAGCAGUAUGUUCACAUCUUAUGUUUAUAUAAAAUUUUCAAAUGUAUGAUAUUUUUGCAUUCUUUUCCUUAAAAGGGGACUCCAAAAAUGUAUACACUUCAGGCUCAACAAAAUUUUGAUCUGCCCCUGCAUGUGGGACCACAUAAGUCUCAGAUACAACACAAAAAUCAUAUUGAUAAAUACCAACUCUUAAGUAAAAAGUUAAGUACAAUGAAUGCCCAGAGAAUUUGAAGAUCUUUUUGUUCCUAUAUUAUCACGAAAUGCUACUUGAAAUUAAAAUGGCUUCAACACUGGCAAAAUGAAGCCUAUUCUUUGAAUUACCCUCAAUGUGUGAAAUUAAUGUUCCAGUAGCAUAAAGACAGUAUUUGAUUUCCCAGAUAUAAUUGACCAUGGGUCAUUAUGUUCAUGGAGCAUCUUAAAGAACUAGUGUUCCAGGAAGCAAACAUUGAUAAUGUCAUGUUAGAGAAGCCUGUCUUUGUUACUGAAGAGCAGAUGAGUAUUACAAUUCCAAAGGAAACAGUAUUAAUGGGUCUGUGUGGAAAUCAGUUCUUAUUUUCUAAACAAUAUUGCUGAUUUCUAGCUAUUUGAGUAAUUUAUAACCUAAUAGAAGAAAAGAAUACUUAAGGAAAAAUGAUUCAUCAGCAUGAAUUUCAAUUAAAAUAACACAGAACUAAUUUUUCCCUUCUGUCCCAGUACAAUUUCAGGGAAUGAGAAGUAAGCAAAUGGAAACCAAGUUAAACUAGACCAUAAAUAGUAAAAUAUGAAGAAAAAAAUUGACAAAUGGCCAGGAAACCAAAUAAAUAAACAGGUUGAUAUUUUAUUUUUCAUUCUUUUGAAAAUGAUAUAGCAUUCUAGAAUAAUUGAAAAAUUUUGAUCUUGAAUAAAAGACUUCAGGAAGGUUAUUUCUUGGAGAACUUCAAUGAAGGGAAAAGGGGGAAAGCAGCCUACAAAAAAAAUUUAGUAUGUGUUGAAAAUGGUUGUAAGUAGAUCUUUGGUCCCAACAGCACAGCUACUAAACUAUGAUAUACGCCAGACCCAAGAUAUUAAAAAAAAAGCCAUAAUGCAACAAAAGUAAUGAUUGGCAAAACCGAUAAUUCAUUAAAAAUCCAUCAGGCCUCCUAAAGGCCAACUUGGUCAUACCUAUACAAUAAAGAAGUGCUGAAACUCCAAUCAGAGUUACACACAAUAUGUAAGUCAAAUAUCUCUUACCAAAUGUUCCAAUAGAUUUUCUUUUUGUAUUAAAUUCGAAUACUUAGAGUACUGGGUUAUGUUCAAUAAUAGGAAGUCACAGCUAAAAGUCGACAAAGAGAAUAACUGAUUGGAAGAACUUUUUCGAUAACAGGAAAUAUGGACAGUUACCUAGGAACUAGGAAAAUAAAAUGACCUGAUGAACUAGCCAUAUCAUUCAUUCAUUAAUCCAUCCAACAAACAUGGAUUAAGAACCUAUAAUGUGCCAAGUGAUGUACAAAGUCCUGUGUGAGGGACAAAGCAGUUCAAAUUGCUCAGCGGAAUACUUUAAUGUCUCAUAAAAAGAAGAAAGUAACUAUUUGCUUUCACUGAAACAUUUGUUAUGAGACAUUGGCAAAACUAGAGUUAUUAUUUAUUUGCCUGCUAUUAACCUAAUUAACCUGCUAUUAAUCUAAAAAUUGUUCAAGAUUCUUAGUUAACAUGUCUUCCAUAAUAAAUAGAAGUUGCUAUACUGAUUUUUUUGUUUGUUGGACAUAAAUGUCAAUGAGUACUAGAUGUGUUUUGGACAAAAUGGUAAGAUAGGAAGGCAAGGAUGCCUAAUGAUUGAUUAGUGUAUUAAACACAGCAGAUACAGCCUUGAGGGUAUACAUCUUUUUGUUUGAAAUUAAUACACUUAAACAAAUUAGUGAAUGUAAGUGUAAAUAGGUUCCCAAACUCAUAAUUUUACCCAAAAGAAAUAAAUACUAGUAAGUAAACAGUCAGGCAAGAAUUGAGACACAAAUAAAAUUUUUUUAAAAAAUAGUUUUAUGAAAGAACAUCAGCAAGGAGUGUUAAUGAGUCGUUUUCUACCCUGUUGCCACCUCUUCUAUUUAGCACAGCAAUGACUAAGACAUAUUUAGAAGGAUGGCCUAAAGAAAAAUCAGGACUAAGUAGUUUAGGUAAAAAGAAGAAUUCAUCUACAGAUGGAGAAAAACAAUCUUGCCCUUCUUCACGCCAAGUUCCAACAUGUUUGAAAUUUAGCACUGGAGGGAUUGGGAGAGCUCAAUAAUUAGACUGCGAUUGAAAUGUUCCACUAAAAUAAUGAUUAGAGAGGCAUCCAGGGGCACUUUCUAUCUUCUUCAUUCGACCUCAGCAUGGAGCACAUCAACUCUGUUUCUUAGUUGGACUAUACUACCUUAGAUACAGAACUGAUUUUUAAAAGUAUAUAAAAUUAUUUCAAGUCUAAAAAUCAUAAAGAGUUUAUCUCAGGAUAAAUAAUUUUUAUGAAAGUAUUUUAUCGCCAGUUCAUUUGUAACCUAAUUGCUUUGCUUAAGUAGAUAAAUCCCAAGCAAUGAGUGAAAUAAACUAGUAGACUAGUGGGUUUUUAACCCUCUACCUAUGUCUCUCAAAUGUUUAUAAUUUCUGCUCCACUAAUAGCCCUGACCCUGCUAGGUAACAAUACUCUAGGAAAUUGAAGAUAUGAGUUCAGAGAAAAAAAAUCAUAAAGGAAGAUAGACAUUGUGAAGAAUGGGCAGUAGUGCUAAUGUAAAGAAAGAAAGAAGGCUGCAUGGAUGAGGGAUUACAUUUUCUGUAGGACAGGAAGAAGAGAUCUACAGAUGUAUAGGUAUAAGCUCUAAGUUGGGAUAAGCAAUGAUGUAGAUUACUAAACAAAAUCAGAUCAUGUGUCUUAUCCACUGAGUUCUACCUUAAUGUUUUUGUUUUCAUGGCUAUAUUCUCAAAAUACCUGAAUUUGUUUUUAGAGUCAUAUAUUUCUUUGUCUUUUCUUAAUUGACAGUUUUAUAUAUUUCUUUCAUUUCUUUCUUGAUUACCUUGAGUUUAACAUCAUGUGCUAUAUGGGAUGAAGAAAAAGUAUGAUGUGUUUUCUACCUUUAAAUUGCUUGCAAUCUCUUUAAAGAUGCUGACAGAAGAAAUAGUCACUCACAAUAAAGCACAAGAAAUGAUUGCAUGAUUCAUACUUUAGAGUUAAGAGAAUCUGGGUAUAGGGAACUAUUGGCAUUAAAGGGGAAUACUUCAAGAAGGAAAUGCAGCUUCAAAUAGGCCUUGAAGAAGGCAUUUUAUCUGCCUAAACAAAAGAACCAUCUCUUCACAGACAUUAACUUGGGUGGGAGAUUCACGAAAGAGGGGAAGCCCCACCCAGUCUGUUCCCCUGUCUCCUGCUCUGACCACUUCUCCAGCCACUGCCCCCUUUGUUCUCUCUGCAUCAACCAUGCACCCCCUUUGGUCUUUUGUCAUUGCAGUUCCCACCACCCUGAAUGCUCUUCUUCCCCCAGUUAGCCACAGAUCUUCCUCCCUCACAUCUUUUUGGUUUCUUCUUAAAUAUUAAAUAAGUAUGCAUUAGAGAGGCCUUUCCUGACAAUCUCAUGAAAAUAUAGUAAAUCUCCUCCCUUCUUUCAUAUUUGUCAUGGGAUUUGUUUAUUGUCUGUCUGUCCCCAGUAAAUUGAAAGCUCUAAGGGGGCAGAGAUAUUUUUCUGCUCUGUAAACUGCUAUAAGCCCAGUACCCUGAAGGGUGCCAGGCACAUGUUAGGCAUUCAAUAAAUAUUUGACAAAGGAAGGAAGGAAAGGAGGGAGGGAGGGAAGAAAUUAGUUCAGGUAGACCUUGAAAGCUUCAAGUGUUUCAGUUGCAAAUAUAUUAGAUGUAUCUCAUUAUCUAGUAAGUCAUUUUAAGGUAAACUUACUGAUACAUUUGAAAGUUGUUUGCCCAUGAAUUCUUUGCUAGGUAAUAUUAACAUCUACCCCUGCACUCCCUUAAAUAUUUAUCAGUAGCUUAAACUUUAACAAAAGACAUGGUUUCCUUUGGCAGAGCAGGGACUGUGCUCGUAUCCUAGCUUGUCAAUGGAAAGAAAAAGAAAUACUGCUGAACAAGUGAAAGAUUAUCAUGGCAGCCACAUCCUUAAAUGGGAGCAAUUGGUAGCCUGCUGCUUCUCAGGCUUAAAGAAGUAAAAGAUACUGCCCCAAGCCAUUUUCAGCUGGAAUUGUAAGAGUAUGCACACAAAUACACAAAGUUACCCUGACAUAAGCGUGAAUAAAAUAUAUUAUCUGAUGCUCAGGAACAUUUCCUUCUUCCCUCAAAAUGAAUAAUUUAUUGGUUUUCUACCUGCUGUUUCCAAGCUCACAUUAAUGAUUCAUUGAUUAGUCUCAAAAACAGAUGCUUGUAAUUAAAUCAUAGGUUCUGUAAGAUCAUUAACUGGUUCUCUAAUGGCUGAAAGAAUUAAGGAGAAAUGGGGUAGUUUAAAUUCAUAGAUUCAAGAAGGAUUAUAGGAAGCAUAUUCUGUACAAAUGUGACAUUUGCUGUAUUGUUUUCCUUUCUGAUAGAAAUUUCUCACCUUCUAAAUUUUCAUUUGUAUGGAACUUGUUUUAGUUUUCUUAACAUCAGCAGGUUUAUUAUUUAUUCCACCCACAGAAAUUCUGACUCAGAUGGCUAGUGCAGUGUAGCCUUGUUACUUGUGUUCAGAUUUCUUAUUGCUCUUUGUUUUAUGCCUUAGUUUAUCCUUAUUAGAAUCUCUCCAAAAUAAUUGAUAAUUUAUGUUGGUCAAGUAGCAUUCCAUUAUCUGUGGUAAAAAAUGCUUUAUUAAUUAUACCACAUAGGUUUCAGCAUGUGCAAAGUCUUCUGAAAGUAUCAUAAAUGAUAGUUGUUUGGGAGAUGUGAUAACUUUUAUUUCCAUUAAUGUUUACAUUUCUGCCUCAUUCUCAGCUGAGAUUGUUACUUAUAUUUUUAUCCACUUGAAUCUUGAAGUUAAGGUAAGCUGAAUAUAUCUAAUUGUCUUUCAUACACAUUACUUUGUUCUACAGAAGAAAUUUAUUAAUGGAGUAAGGUGAAUAUGAUAAACUCAAAUCAGAUUUUCUUCUUAUGUCUGCCCCUGAAUCCAAAAUUGGGGGUGCCUGCUAUAAAAUCAAGUAUGUUUAUGAAAACCUUCCCUCUCCUAUAAUUGCUGGAGUAUUCAUUCAGAGCUCUCACUUGCUAUAUAAUUUCUAACCAAACACUUUCCAGGGAAUGUACAACAAGGAAGUACAUGGACAACACUCAAAUUCAAAUGUCCAUAGAUGGUGGAAUUUUACCACUCUUUAGCUUACAAGCUCAAUCAACUGAAACGUUUCAGAAAUGUUUGUGUUUGGGGUUUGGGUUUGAGAUGUGAAACAAAUGACAUCCUUAAACAUGUUAUUGUUAGUCUUCAAGGUACAUAUGUGUACCUUGAUAUAGAACUAUUUAUAGUUACAGUUUGCUAAAAAAUUAUUAUAAUGAAAUUAACUUUGGGAGGUAGAUGUUAAAGUACCAGCUUGUAAAAAGAAUGUUUAAUGCCAAUCAUUUGUAUGUUUAAUACCUGUGUGCUCAAUGUAGUGUCAUCUUUACUAGAUGAUUUACUUCACAAUGUUUUCAUUCCUGUUCCCCAAAUGAAAAUAAGUAGUCUAUUAACUAAUUUACAGCUCUUAGUUUUGGAUACUAUUGCAGAGACACAGGAGCACUUUUAACUCAAACACUAUGGUUUACCAUAGUUUUGCGGUGGUAUGAAAUUGAGUUAGCACUGCAAUGCAAUAUUGAAAAAAUCAGAAUGCAAUAAAGAAAUGUAGAUAUCACCUGUGACUACUUCAUGUACUACCCAGACUCCUCAUUUAUUGUUUGAACCCAAGGGUUAGUUUUUUAUCUUGCCAAAAGGACAUGAUCAGGAAGUCAGUGUGAUACCGUCUUGCUGCAGUGCAGAAGUUUUAAGAAGCAAGAUACUUUUUAAUGAUGUACUAUCACAGGAUAGAAGUUAUGCCCUACAUGAAACUACGUAUUCGCAGAAACUUUGUGUCGUCAAUGUGCAUCUGUUCUUACUAGUCUGGAGGGAAACAAAUAAGAUUUCCAGUUUUCUGCUGAUCCAACACCAUUUCCCAUAGGCAGCACAAUACACCAGCACACAGUUAGCAGCACUUUGGGACAAAACUGUUGAAAGGAAAGAAACAGUGAUUAUUCUGAAAACAUGUAAAGCAACACUGAUCAUAAGUAAUUUUUGUUAGGUGGGACAAUACUAUAUAAUAUGAUUUCUUGUGUCUAAAUUUUCUCUAAAAGAUUAUUUGGGCUGGGUCCAGAAGGCUCCAAUUUCCCUAAGCAACCUUGAUCAUCAAUGUUGUCAUGCUUCAGCUUUUGGCAGUUUUGAUUCAUUACCAAUUAUUAAUAUCAUUAUUUAAAUAUGAAUAUUGUCCCUUCCCAUUAUGAAAAGCUAUUACAAACAUAUAUGGAUUUAUAUAAAGGUUGAUGACUAUAUGCUUUUUUAUAUUAGAAAAUCAUGUGAAAACAAAAUUAAUCUGAUGAAUGCUGUUAAUUAUUUUAACUUUUUUAUUAGGUAUAAAAUGUUCAUAAAAUUAUUCUCUCUAUAACUUACCAAGAUUUAUUAGCUUGUGUAAUUUUUAUAAUCAGAGGAGUCUGGUUUUCUAAUUAAAGUUUUGUCAAAGAAAA